GGAAGUCCGUAGUGUCUCAUUGCAGAUAAUUUUUAGCUUAGGGCCUGGUGGCUAGGUCGGUUCUCUCCUUUCCAGUCGGAGACCUCUGCCGCAAACAUGCUCCGCCAGAUCAUCGGUCAGGCCAAGAAGCAUCCGAGCUUGAUCCCCCUCUUUGUAUUUAUUGGAACUGGAGCUACUGGAGCAACACUGUAUCUCUUGCGUCUGGCAUUGUUCAAUCCAGAUGUUUGUUGGGACAGAAAUAACCCAGAGCCCUGGAACAAACUGGGUCCCAAUGAUCAAUACAAGUUCUACUCAGUGAAUGUGGAUUACAGCAAGCUGAAGAAGGAACGUCCAGAUUUCUAAAUGAAAUGUUUCACUAUAACGCUGCUUUAGAAUGAAGGUCUUCCAGAAGCCACAUCCGCACAAUUUUCCACUUAACCAGGAAAUAUUUCUCCUCUAAAUGCAUGAAAUCAUGUUGGAGAUCUCUAUUGUAAUCUCUAUUGGAGAUUACAAUGAUUAAAUCAAUAAAUAACUGAAACUUGAUAUGUGUCACUUUUUUAUGCUGAAAGUAUGCUCUGAACUUUAGAGUAUAGGAAAUUAACUAUUAGAAUUUAAAGAAUUUCUUGAAUUUCUGUAGUUUGAAAAUACGACUUUAAGCUGCUUUAGUAAAACACUUCCAUUUUGUGUAUAGACUGUUGGUAACUUCACUAGAGCAUACAUAACAACUGGAACUGGAAAUUAUACAAAAGUAAAUUGGGAAGGAUACUCCAGCAUCUGACACUGGCAAAAUGGAAACCUUUGAGUUUCUCUUACUGGCUGUUGAAGUGUGUGCAGUUUUUAACAAUGGUUUUUACUUGGCAUCUCUUUGUUGUGAUUUUCAAGGUUAUAAGUUGCUUUGGUCCUAGGAUUGAAGUUGAAAUCUGAGUUUAUCAGUGCUAACCAUGGUGCUAGUAGUCAAGAGAUCUUGAGAAUUUUGGCUGCUGAGUCUUGGUGCAGGGUGCAGGUUUUCUUUUCUUUUUUCUUUUUUUUUUUUUUGAGAUAGUCUCUGUCACCCAGGCUGGAGUGCAGUGGUACAAACAUGGAUCACUGCAGCCUCUACCUCCCGGGCUUAAGUGAUCCUCCUGCCUCAGCCCCUAAGUAGCCGGGACUACAGGUAUGUGCCACCAUGCCCAGUUAAUUUUUGUAAUUUUUUUUAGAGACAGGGUUUUGCCAUGUUGCCCAGGCUGGUCUCAAACUCUUGAGCUCAAGCGAUCCAUUCUCCUCAGCCUCCCAGGGUGCUGGGAUUACAGGCGUGAGCCAUUGCGCUUAGCCAUGGUGCAGGUUUUCAAAGGCCAGGAAGUAUAUUCAUAAUUUUAAGAUGGGGAAUAUAGCAAGUUUUCACAUAGGUGUGUGUAAGUCAUCACAUCAUAGAAACUUGAGGAAUUCAGUGACAUUAAUUUUGGAUUUUCAUACGUAAGUAUACAAUUAAAUGUUUACAGGGUAGUAGAAGCACAUUUUAAAUGUCAGGAACUGAACUAAGUAUUUGAAUUACGUGGAUUAUCUCAAAAAUUUUGAAAUUGUUAAACGAGUUGAAUUACUUGAAUUCAUUCUGUUAGUCAAAUGGUGGAUAUUUACACCCAUGUAGUUUUGAAUUUAGAGUGUGUAGAGUGUUUUCAGUUACCAGACUCCAUGCUUUUACCUCCUAUGUGUCAGGUAUAAUUUGAACCUCUAAGAACAGGGUUUCUCAACCUUGCCACUGUUGACUAUUUCUGAAAGACAGUUUGGUUUAGCAGACCAUCCCAUGCGCUUUAGCUUGUUUAGUAGCUAACUUGGGCUCUGCCACUACAGACAAAAAGCACUCUUUCCCUCCAAUUCCCACAGGCUAUGAGAAGAAUGGAGACAUUACCAAAUGUCCAUUGGUGGGCAAAAUUGCUUCAUUCCUACCUCUGUUGAGAAUUACUCUAGAUCCUUUGGCACAAAUUACCUCAAAGUUUAAAAUUGUGUAAACAAACAGUGUGUCAUGUAAUUGAAAAACAUUAAGCAACUCCAAAUAAAUGCUACAUUAAGAAAUUAGUAA